GCACUUGAUGGGAAUCAUGGCAGCAUCCAGGCCAUUGUCCCGCUUCUGGGAGUGGGGAAAGAACAUCGUCUGCGUGGGGAGGAACUACGCGGACCACGUCAGGGAGAUGCGCAGCGCGGUGUUGAGCGAGCCCGUGCUGUUCCUGAAGCCGUCCACGGCCUACGCGCCCGAGGGCUCGCCCAUCCUCAUGCCCGCGUACACUCGCAACCUGCACCACGAGCUGGAGCUGGGCGUGGUGAUGGGCAAGCGCUGCCGCGCAGUCCCCGAGGCUGCGGCCAUGGACUACGUGGGCGGCUAUGCCCUGUGCCUGGAUAUGACCGCCCGGGACGUGCAGGACGAGUGCAAGAAGAAGGGGCUGCCCUGGACUCUGGCGAAGAGCUUCACGGCGUCCUGCCCGGUCAGCGCGUUCGUGCCCAAGGAGAAGAUCCCUGACCCUCACAAGCUGAAGCUCUGGCUCAAGGUCAACGGCGAACUCAGACAGGAGGGUGAGACAUCCUCCAUGAUUUUUUCCAUCCCCUACAUCAUCAGCUAUGUUUCUAAGAUCAUAACCUUGGAAGAAGGAGAUAUUAUCUUGACUGGGACGCCAAAGGGAGUUGGACCGGUUAAAGAAAACGAUGAGAUCGAGGCUGGCAUACACGGGCUGGUCAGUAUGACAUUUAAAGUGGAAAAGCCAGAAUAUUGAGUUAUUUCUUAACAAGUUUCGAGAGAGAAGGGAGCAAGACAAGAGCAAGCAACGGCUAUUAAAUGUCACAAUCCUUUAAUUAGAAACCAUUUAUUGGCCGGACGCGGUGGCUCACGCCUGUAAUCGCAGCACUUUGGGAGGCCGAGGCGGGCGGCUCACGACGUCAGGAGAUCCAGACCAUCUUGGCUAACAGGGUGAAACCCCGUCUCUACUAAAAAUACAAAAAAUUAGCCGGGCGUGGUGGCGGGCGCCUGUAGUCCCAGCUACUCUGGAGGCUGAGGCAGGAGAAUCAAUUGAACCCGGGAGGCGGAGCUUACAGUGAGCUGAGAUUGCGCCACUGUACUCCUGGGCAACAGCGAGACUCCGUCUCAAAAAAAAAAAAAAAAAAAGAAACCAUUUAUUUUAAAAAUGAUUAGAUUGCUAUGCCUCAACUCAUAGAAGAUGAACCCUUCAAGAAAACGUGAAGUAGAACGGGUGGGCCAGAAAUGAAAACAGGCAAGUAAAGUAUUUCUUCGGAAAACAUUUUAUCAAACCAAAUGUUAAAAAGACUUUCCUUUUGUAAAACUGGAUUAGAGAAGACUUUUCAGUGGGUUAUCUCUAGGAUGAUCAGUAGUUCAGCACUUAAAAACUGCAGAGAAAACUGAAAGUUAUGUUCCAGAUAACUUUCCGUUGUUUACCAAAUUUUCUUAGAUUUGGUCAUCAUCAGGAAGCAUUUGUAAAAAUAAAAAUCUCCACAAAUUACUGGCCCAUCUCGGACUUGCUGAAUCAAUUUGAUAGGAUUAAUCUCCAGUGAAGCUGUGUUUACAGGGCAUUCCAAGUGAUUCUUAUCAGGAAAUGUGAAAAACACUCCUGUACAUAAUCGGUUAAUUUAAAAUUUUACUUAAUAAGUGAACAAGUAAUGAAGAUUUCACCUGUUUACUUAGGGUAUCUACCCAGACCCAUCGAUUCUGAGUUCGGGAGAUGAUUUUGAAAUUACUGUUUUCCAAAUAAAGGUGCUCCCUUCUAAGUGGCUUACAAGGGUAAUUUUUUUCCCCCCAGUAAUGACGAGGAGGGAUAUUUCCUCCUUGUGGGGCUUCAGACCUUAGUCUUUGACCUUUGGCCUUCUGAGCACUGUGCUGUGUUAACACAGUUAAUCAGCAACUGUACUUCCCAACCGGAGAUAAGGAGGCUUUGUGGAAGUUGAAUAGCCUGGGACUGCUGCUUUUGCUCUUGCCUGCACCCUCCUCUGAAAAAACAUCCAGGCAAGAUGCACAGCAUAGCUGUCAAUGCCUGGAGGAGUCCUUUGGGCUUCGGCAGGGGUUCCUGUUCGCGUUCACAUCAUCUGCUGGCCCCUGAAGAAAGCCUAGGACAUCUGAUUGAGUAGUAACGGUCCCCAUGUAUUGAACACAGUACUGUUAGGCACCAUGCCAAGCAGUUUAUUCUGUAUUUCCACGUGUUAUGUAACCAGCAACCAAGCCAUAAGCUUAGUAUGAUCACUACCAUCCCCAUUACUCAGAUGAAGACAGAUCUAGAGGCUGCGAAGGCUGGCUAAAGUCACUCAGCUUAGUGGCAGAGCCGAGAUGUAACCCAGCUCCCCCAAGACCAGAACGUGAAGUUUUGACCACAAUGCAGGCUGCAUCUUAGACAGGGUCUCACUCUGUCGCCCAAGCUGGAGUGCAGCAGUGCUAUCACAGCUCACUGCAGCCUCGAACUCCCGGGGUCAAGCAAUCCUCCCUCAGCUUCCCGUUUCUGAGGUUACAGCCCAAAGUCUCCUCAGCAACACUUCCUGUGAGACUACAGGAAUGAAGGGUGCCUGUGUGAUCAGUCAGAUCAAUCAGCACAUGGAAACUGAGAAAGACAGAUUUAAAGUCCAAGGAGUUUUUGUUGCAAGUUGUGCACAUGUUAGAUGCUUCAUUUACAAUAUAACCACAGCUGGAACUGAAAAGAAACAAAGACAAUGAUAAAAUGUGAUGCCCUAAGCUACAAAUUUCAUCUGUAGCAGAAAAAGAAUUGUCACUAAAAACUCUACGACAGUGUGUGGAAAACUUACUGAGUGUUCAGUGCUAUGCGGUCUACAAGACAGUCGUAAAAAACAGUAAAACACACUUUCUACGCAGCCAUUCUCAGGAGUCAUCUGAAACUGCGUACACCAGUCCUCUGCCUGCCCUCCUUCCCUCCCUCUGCCAAGCCCUCGAGGUCCAUCCCAGUCUCAUUUCCUUGCUGGGGCCCUCCCUUCUCGUAUCCCAGCCUGCAGCCUUUCUCUCUUGGAACAGCAGCAGAGUGCACGCCUCAGGACUGACUGGUGCUGUUGCAUCAGCUCCUUAUUCUCACCUCCCUGGCUGGGAGUUCUGAGGGCAGGAACUGUGUCUUGUGCCUGGAAAGCACGAGUUCAACAGCUGCUCACUGGAUGGGCCUGCACGGGGCCUUCUCUACAAAUACAGAAAGCCUUGCAAGGCUGGCCGGGUAGCACCCAGAUGCUAUUAACACUGCUGGUGAUACACUCUCCUCUCUUUCAGUGAUUUAUGCUAUUCCAUAUUUCUGAAGCAAGCCUUACUUUAGCAAUUUUAAACAGGGAAACUAAUUCAAAUUUCUCAAAUAGGGGAAAUGAACUGAAGAUAGUGGUUUCUUAUCUAGCCACAGAUCACUUGGUCUAGCAAAUUUUAGAUGCUUUUCCUCAGAUAUCAAUAAUAAAUGUACAGGAAAAAAA